GUGUACUGUGUGCGCCGGGGAGGCGCCGGCUUGUACUCGGCAGCGCGGGAAUAAAGUUUGCUGAUUUGGUGUCUAGCCUGGAUGCCUGGGUUGCAGGCCCUGCUUGUGGUGGCGCUCCACAGUCAUCCGGCUGAAGAAGACCUGUUGGACUGGAUCUUCUCGGGUUUUCUUUCAGAUAUUGUUUUGUAUUUACCCAUGAAGACAUUGUUUUUUGGACUCUGCAAAUAGGACAUUUCAAAGAUGAGUGAAAAAAAAUUGGAAACAACUGCACAGCAGCGGAAAUGUCCUGAAUGGAUGAAUGUGCAGAAUAAAAGAUGUGCUGUAGAAGAAAGAAAGGCAUGUGUUCGGAAGAGUGUUUUUGAAGAUGACCUCCCCUUCUUAGAAUUCACUGGAUCCAUUGUGUAUAGUUACGAUGCUAGUGAUUGCUCUUUCCUGUCAGAAGAUAUUAGCAUGAGUCUAUCAGAUGGGGAUGUGGUGGGAUUUGACAUGGAGUGGCCACCAUUAUACAAUAGAGGGAAACUUGGCAAAGUUGCACUAAUUCAGUUGUGUGUUUCUGAGAGCAAAUGUUACUUGUUCCACGUUUCUUCCAUGUCAGUUUUUCCCCAGGGAUUAAAAAUGUUGCUUGAAAAUAAAGCAGUUAAAAAGGCAGGUGUAGGAAUUGAAGGAGAUCAGUGGAAACUUCUACGUGACUUUGAUAUCAAAUUGAAGAAUUUUGUGGAGUUGACAGAUGUUGCCAAUAAAAAGCUGAAAUGCACAGAGACCUGGAGCCUUAACAGUCUGGUUAAACACCUCUUAGGUAAACAGCUCCUGAAAGACAAGUCUAUCCGCUGUAGCAAUUGGAGUAAAUUUCCUCUCACUGAGGACCAGAAACUGUAUGCAGCCACUGAUGCUUAUGCUGGUUUUAUUAUUUACCGAAAUUUAGAGAUUUUGGAUGAUACUGUGCAAAGGUUUGCUAUAAAUAAAGAGGAAGAAAUCCUACUUAGCGACAUGAACAAACAGUUGACUUCAAUCUCUGAGGAAGUGAUGGAUCUGGCUAAGCAUCUUCCUCAUGCUUUCAGUAAAUUGGAAAACCCACGGAGGGUUUCUAUCUUACUAAAGGAUAUUUCAGAAAAUCUAUAUUCACUGAGGAGGAUGAUAAUUGGGUCUACUAACAUUGAGACUGAACUGAGGCCCAGCAAUAAUUUAAACUUAUUAUCCUUUGAAGAUUCAACUACUGGGGGAGUACAACAGAAACAAAUUAGAGAACAUGAAGUUUUAAUUCACGUUGAAGAUGAAACAUGGGACCCAACACUUGAUCAUUUAGCUAAACAUGAUGGAGAAGAUGUACUUGGAAAUAAAGUGGAACGAAAAGAAGAUGGAUUUGAAGAUGGAGUAGAAGACAACAAAUUGAAAGAGAAUAUGGAAAGAGCUUGUUUGAUGUCGUUAGAUAUUACAGAACAUGAACUCCAAAUUUUGGAACAGCAGUCUCAGGAAGAAUAUCUUAGUGAUAUUGCUUAUAAAUCUACUGAGCAUUUAUCUCCCAAUGAUAAUGAAAACGAUACGUCCUAUGUAAUUGAGAGUGAUGAAGAUUUAGAAAUGGAGAUGCUUAAGCAUUUAUCUCCCAAUGAUAAUGAAAACGAUACGUCCUAUGUAAUUGAGAGUGAUGAAGAUUUAGAAAUGGAGAUGCUUAAGUCUUUAGAAAACCUCAAUAGUGGCACGGUAGAACCAACUCAUUCUAAAUGCUUAAAAAUGGAAAGAAAUCUGGGUCUUCCUACUAAAGAAGAAGAAGAAGAUGAUGAAAAUGAAGCUAAUGAAGGGGAAGAAGAUGAUGAUAAGGACUUUUUGUGGCCAGCACCCAAUGAAGAGCAAGUUACUUGCCUCAAGAUGUACUUUGGCCAUUCCAGUUUUAAACCAGUUCAGUGGAAAGUGAUUCAUUCAGUAUUAGAAGAAAGAAGAGAUAAUGUUGCUGUCAUGGCAACUGGAUAUGGAAAGAGUUUGUGCUUCCAGUAUCCACCUGUUUAUGUAGGCAAGAUUGGCCUUGUUAUCUCUCCCCUUAUUUCUCUGAUGGAAGACCAAGUGCUACAGCUUAAAAUGUCCAACAUCCCAGCUUGCUUCCUUGGAUCAGCACAGUCAGAAAAUGUUCUAACAGAUAUUAAAUUAGGUAAAUACCGGAUUGUAUACGUAACUCCAGAAUACUGUUCAGGUAACAUGGGCCUGCUCCAGCAACUUGAGGCUGAUAUUGGUAUCACGCUCAUUGCUGUGGAUGAGGCUCACUGUAUUUCUGAGUGGGGGCAUGAUUUUAGGGAUUCAUUCAGGAAGUUGGGCUCCCUAAAGACAGCACUGCCAAUGGUUCCAAUCGUUGCACUUACUGCUACUGCAAGUUCUUCAAUCCGGGAAGACAUUGUACGUUGCUUAAAUCUGAGAAAUCCUCAGAUCACCUGUACUGGUUUUGAUCGACCAAACCUGUAUUUAGAAGUUAGGCGAAAAACAGGGAAUAUCCUUCAGGAUCUGCAGCCAUUUCUUGUCAAAACAAGUUCCCACUGGGAAUUUGAAGGUCCAACAAUCAUCUACUGUCCUUCUAGAAAAAUGACACAACAAGUUACAGGUGAACUUAGGAAACUGAAUCUAUCCUGUGGAACAUACCAUGCGGGCAUGAGUUUUAGCACAAGGAAAGACAUUCAUCAUAGGUUUGUAAGAGAUGAAAUUCAGUGUGUCAUAGCUACCAUAGCUUUUGGAAUGGGCAUUAAUAAAGCUGACAUUCGCCAAGUCAUUCAUUACGGUGCUCCUAAGGACAUGGAAUCAUAUUAUCAGGAGAUUGGUAGAGCUGGUCGUGAUGGACUUCAAAGUUCUUGUCACGUCCUCUGGGCUCCUGCAGACAUUAACUUAAAUAGGCACCUUCUUACUGAGAUACGUAAUGAGAAGUUUCGAUUAUACAAAUUAAAGAUGAUGGCAAAGAUGGAAAAAUAUCUUCAUUCUAGCAGAUGUAGGAGACAAAUCAUCUUGUCUCAUUUUGAGGACAAACAAGUACAAAAAGCCUCCUUGGGAAUUAUGGGAACUGAAAAAUGCUGUGAUAAUUGCAGGUCCAGAUUGGAUCAUUGCUAUUCCAUGGAUGACUCAGAGGAUACAUCCUGGGACUUUGGUCCACAAGCAUUUAAGCUUUUGUCUGCUGUGGACAUCUUAGGCGAAAAAUUUGGAAUUGGGCUUCCAAUUUUAUUUCUCCGAGGAUCUAAUUCUCAGCGUCUUGCCGAUCAAUAUCGCAGGCACAGUUUAUUUGGCACUGGCAAGGAUCAAACAGAGAGUUGGUGGAAGGCUUUUUCCCGUCAGCUGAUCACUGAGGGAUUCUUGGUAGAAGUUUCUCGGUAUAACAAAUUUAUGAAGAUUUGCGCCCUUACGAAAAAGGGUAGAAAUUGGCUUCAUAAAGCUAAUACAGAAUCUCAGAGCCUCAUCCUUCAAGCUAAUGAAGAAUUGUGUCCAAAGAAGUUGCUUCUGCCUAGUUCGAAAACUGUAUCUUCGGGCACCAAAGAGCAUUGUUAUAAUCAAGUACCAGUUGAAUUAAGUACAGAGAAGAAGUCUAACUUGGAGAAGUUAUAUUCUUAUAAACCAUGUGAUAAGAUUUCUUCUGGGAGUAACAUUUCUAAAAAAAGUAUCAUGGUACAGUCACCAGAAAAAGCUUACAGUUCCUCACAGCCUGUUAUUUCGGCACAAGAGCAGGAGACUCAGAUUGUGUUAUAUGGCAAAUUGGUAGAAGCUAGGCAGAAACAUGCCAAUAAAAUGGAUGUUCCCCCAGCUAUUCUGGCAACAAACAAGAUACUGGUGGAUAUGGCCAAAAUGAGACCAACUACGGUUGAAAACGUAAAAAGGAUUGAUGGUGUUUCUGAAGGCAAAGCUGCCAUGUUGGCCCCUCUGUUGGAAGUCAUCAAACAUUUCUGCCAAACAAAUAGUGUUCAGACAGACCUCUUUUCAAGUACAAAACCUCAAGAAGAACAGAAGACGAGUCUGGUAGCAAAAAAUAAAAUAUGCACACUUUCACAGUCUAUGGCCAUCACAUACUCUUUAUUCCAAGAAAAGAAGAUGCCUUUGAAGAGCAUAGCUGAGAGCAGGAUUCUGCCUCUCAUGACAAUUGGCAUGCACUUAUCCCAAGCGGUGAAAGCUGGCUGCCCCCUUGAUUUGGAGCGAGCAGGCCUGACUCCAGAGGUUCAGAAGAUUAUUGCUGAUGUUAUCCGAAACCCUCCCGUCAACUCAGAUAUGAGUAAAAUUAGCCUAAUCAGAAUGUUAGUUCCUGAAAACAUUGACACGUACCUUAUCCACAUGGCAAUUGAGAUCCUUAAACAUGGUCCUGACAGCGGACUUCAACCUUCAUGUGAUGUCAACAAAAGGAGAUGUUUUCCCGGUUCUGAAGAGAUCUGUUCAAGUUCUAAGAGAAGCAAGGAAGAAGUAGGCAUCAAUACUGAGACUUCAUCUGCAGAGAGAAAGAGACGAUUACCUGUGUGGUUUGCCAAAGGAAGUGAUACCAGCAAGAAAUUAAUGGACAAAACGAAAAGGGGAGGUCUUUUUAGUUAAGCUGGCAAUUACCAGAACAAUUAUGUUUCUUGCUGUAUUAUAAGAGGAUAGCUAUAUUUUAUUUCUGAAGAGUAAGGAGUAGUAUUUUGGCUUAAAAAUCAUUCUAAUUACAAAGUUCACUGUUUAUUGAAGAACUGGCAUCUUAAAUCAGCCUUCCGCAAUUCAUGUAGUUUCUGGGUCUUCUGGGAGCCUACGUGAGUACAUCACCUAACAGAAUAUUAAAUUAGACUUCCUGUAAGAUUGCUUUAAGAAACUGUUACUGUCCUGUUUUCUAAUCUCUUUAUUAAAACAGUGUAUUUGGAAAAUGUUAUGUGCUCUGAUUUGAUAUAGAUAACAGAUUAGUAGUUACAUGGUAAUUAUGUGAUAUAAAAUAUUCAUAUAUUAUCAAAAUUCUGUUUUGUAAAUGUAAGAAAGCAUAGUUAUUUUACAAAUUGUUUUUACUGUCUUUUGAAGAAGUUCUUAAAUACGUUGUUAAAUGGUAUUAGUUGACCAGGGCAGUGAAAAUGAAACCGCAUUUUGGGUGCCAUUAAAUAGGGAAAAAACAUGUAAAAAAUGUAAAAUGGAGACCAAUUGCACUAGGCAAGUGUAUAUUUUGUAUUUUAUAUACAAUUUCUAUUAUUUUUCAAGUAAUAAAACAAUGUUUUUCAUACUGAAUAUUAUAUAUAUAUUUUUUAGCUUUCAUUUACUUAAUUAUUUUAAGUACCUUUAUUUUUCCAGGAUGUCAGAAUUUGAUUCUAAUCUCUCUUAUGUAGCACAUGUGACUUAAUUUAAAACCUAUACUGUGACACAGAGUUGGGUAAACGAUGAUUAUUUAACUUUAAGCAGUUCACCAUCCAUUUCAAAGCCUUUGAUUGGCUUUUUUGUAAAUAAAAAUAACUUGUUAAGAAACAAAUAUAUCUGUCAUAGAAGAACUAGAAAAUCCAGGGAAGUGAGAAAAAUGAAAAUAAAAAUCAUUCAUAGUUUUACUAGUAGCUAAUCACAGUCAACCUCUUUUGUGUAUCCCACCAGACUUUUUUAUAUUCAUUUGUUUUUAGUUAAAAUAUAAAAGUCUCGUAUAUUCCCAUUUUUCUGCAUUGCAUUACCAGAAGGUAGUGGCGCCUAUUAAAUAUGUGAUAUGUUGUUGUCCAGCCAUGGCUUCUGCAUUUGCAUGCUUUUGUGUGUGCAUCUGCAAUACCCUGUGAAUAUCCUGUGUGAUGGAGUGGCAAGUACGCACAGACACGUCUGCUGCAUGCCUAGGUACGAGGCUGUCUCCAGGAGAAGCACUUGUUUGAUUAUUUGAGUUGCCAAUUGAAUUUGCUGCUUUUUUUCAUGGCUUGCCAUUUUCACUGAAAAGAAUGACUAAUGAAAAACGAUGAUUGGUUAUUAGAUUUGGAUGUUUGGCAGACAUUUUCUCAAAAUUGAACUAAGUUGGCCUCUUCACGGAAAACAACUGGUAUUUGUUGUGCCAAUGAUAAAAUUGGAGAUUUCUAGCAAAAUGUAUAAUUUUGGAAAAGUUGUGUUCCUCCACUGGAAGCUUGACAGCUUUCCUUAACAUAAAGACUUCUCUUUCUCUUCGCUUUCACUACUACUACUACUAAUUCUUCUUCUGAUUCUUCUUCUUCUCCUUCUUCCUUCUUCCUUCCUUCCUCCUCCUCCUCCUUCUUCUUCCUCUUCCUCUUCUUCUUUCUCUCUUUCCUUCCUUCCCUUCCCUUCCCCUUCCUUCCUUCCUUCCUUCCUUCCUCCCUCCCUCCCUCCCUCCCUCCCUCCCUCCUUUCUUUUUCUUUCUCUUUCUUUCUUUCUUUCUCUCUCUCUCUCUCUUUCUUUCUUUUUCUUUCUCUUUUUCUUUCUUUCAAGCAGUCCUCCCGCCUCAGUCCCCCAAAAUAGUGGGAUUACAGGUGUGAGCCACCAUGCACAGCCUUACAUAAAGCCUUUUCUAAUGAGAUGGAUAGUAAUUAACAAAUGUGAGUUUUUGAUAUUAUAUAAAGAUUUUUUCUGUGUUUCGAAGAUCCGUAUAACUCAGUGAAUCAGUAUGUUCUGGAUGACUAAUAUGUGAUGUUAAGAAAUCAUGACUGAGGCCGGGCGCGGUGGCUCACGCCUGUAAUCCCAGCACUUUGGGAGGCCGAGGCGGGCGGAUCACGAGAUCAGGAGAUCGAGACCACCCUGGCCAACAUGGUGAAACCCCGUCUCUACUAAAAAUACAAAAAUUAGCUGGGUGUGUUGGUGCGUGCCUAUAAUCCCAGCUACUCGGGAGGCUGAGGCAGGAGAAUCGCUUGAACUCAGGAGGCGGAGAUUGCAGUGAGCUGAGACUGCGCCACUGCACCCCAGCCUGGCGACAGAGCAAGACUCCGUCUCAAAAAUAAAAAAAGAAAUCAUGACUGGGUAAAAGAUCUGUUCAGAGUACAAGAUGGACCAAUGGAUUUGAUAUAUUUGAAUAUAACAGAGUAUGAAAAAGUUUAUUGAUAUAGUUUCAGAUUACACACUGCAACUAAUCUUUAAGAAACUAUUACUUGUCCACUUUUUGGUAAAAUUUCAGAGAACAAUGUCCACCAUUAUCUGAACAGGCUAUUAAAAUACUCUUCUCUUUUCCAACUACGUGCCUGUGCAAAGUCAGAUUUUUUUCAUAUACUUCAGCCAAAACAGCAUAUCAAAAUGGAUUGAAUGCAGAAGUAGAUCUGAGAAUACAGCCACUUUUGUUAAGCCAGACAAUGAGAUUUGCAAAAUGUAAACAAUGCUGCUGUUCUCAGUUUUUAAAAAUAUGUUUUUUAAAAGUAUUUAUGUUAAUGUGUACUUGGUUUACUACUGCUAUUUUUAAAUAAAACAAGAAACAUUUUUAAAUGUCUGUUUUAAUUUCUAAAGUGGUAGUGAUAGAUAUAACCCAUAUUAAUAAAAGCUCUUUGGGGUCCUCAGUGAUUUUUUUUUAAGAGUAUGGAAGGGUUCUCAGACCUAAGAGAUUGAGAAAUGCUGAUGUAAUGUUUUAUUAUAAAGGUGUACCAUGAAUUAUGUACCUUACUUCAUAUUGUUGGACAUUAAAGUUGCUUUCAGUUUUUUUGUUUUAAA